GCUCUUGUCGAUUUCCUGUAGUGAAUCAGGCACCGGAGUGCAGGUUCGGGGGUGGAAUCCUUGGGCCGCUGGGCAAGCGGCGAGACCUGGCCAGGGCCAGCGAGCCGAGGACAGAGGGCGCACGGAGGGCCGGGCCGCAGCCCCGGCCGCUUGCAGACCCCGCCAUGGACCCGUUCCUGGUGCUGCUGCACUCGGUGUCGUCCAGCCUGUCGAGCAGCGAGCUGACCGAGCUCAAGUUCCUAUGCCUCGGGCGCGUGGGCAAGCGCAAGCUGGAGCGCGUGCAGAGCGGCCUAGACCUCUUCUCCAUGCUGCUGGAGCAGAACGACCUGGAGCCCGGGCACACCGAGCUCCUGCGCGAGCUGCUCGCCUCCCUGCGGCGCCACGACCUGCUGCGGCGCGUCGACGACUUCGAGGCGGGGGCGGCGGCCGGGGCCGCGCCUGGGGAAGAAGACCUGUGUGCAGCAUUUAACGUCAUAUGUGAUAAUGUGGGGAAAGAUUGGAGAAGGCUGGCUCGUCAGCUCAAAGUCUCAGACACCAAGAUCGACAGCAUCGAGGACAGAUACCCCCGCAACCUGACAGAGCGUGUGCGGGAGUCACUGAGAAUCUGGAAGAACACAGAGAAGGAGAACGCAACAGUGGCCCACCUGGUGGGGGCUCUCAGGUCCUGCCAGAUGAACCUGGUGGCUGACCUGGUACAAGAGGUUCAGCAGGCCCGUGACCUCCAGAACAGGAGUGGGGCCAUGUCCCCGAUGUCAUGGAACUCAGACGCAUCUACCUCCGAAGCGUCCUGAUGGGCCGCUGCUUUGCGCUGGUGGACCACAGGCAUCUACACAGCCUGGACUUUGGUUCUCUCCAGGAAGGUAGCCCAGCACUGUGAAGACCCAGCAGGAAGCCAGGCUGAGUGAGCCACAGACCACCUGCUUCUGAACUCAAGCUGCGUUUAUUAAUGCCUCUCCCGCACCAGGCCGGGCUUGGGCCCUGCACAGAUAUUUCCAUUUCUUCCUCACUAUGACACUGAGCAAGAUCUUGUCUCCACUAAAUGAGCUCCUGCGGGAGUAGUUGGAAAGUUGGAACCGUGUCCAGCACAGAAGGAAUCUGUGCAGAUGAGCAGUCACACUGUUACUCCACAGCGGAGGAGACCAGCUCAGAGGCCCAGGAAUCGGAGCGAAGCAGAGAGGUGGAGAACUGGGAUUUGAACCCCCGCCAUCCUUCACCAGAGCCCAUGCUCAACCACUGUGGCGUUCUGCUGCCCCUGCAGUUGGCAGAAAGGAUGUUUUGUCCCAUUUCCUUGGAGGCCACCGGGACAGACCUGGACACUAGGGUCAGGCGGGGUGCUGUGGUGGGGAGAGGCAUGGCUGGGGUGGGGGUGGGGAGACCUGGUUGGCCGUGGUCCAGCUCUUGGCCCCUGUGUGAGUUGAGUCUCCUCUCUGAGACUGCUAAGUAGGGGCAGUGAUGGUUGCCAGGACGAAUUGAGAUAAUAUCUGUGAGGUGCUGAUGAGUGAUUGACACACAGCACUCUCUAAAUCUUCCUUGUGAGGAUUAUGGGUCCUGCAAUUCUACAGUUUCUUACUGUUUUGUAUCAAAAUCACUAUCUUUCUGAUAACAGAAUUGCCAAGGCAGCGGGAUCUCGUAUCUUUAAAAAGCAGUCCUCUUAUUCCUAAGGUAAUCCUAUUAAAACACAGCUUUACAACUUCCAUACUACAAAAAA